AGCCGCCCGCCCCGGCCGCCCGCCCGCCCCGCCCGCGCGCCCGCCGCCCCCGGCCCCCCGGGUCCCCCCUCGGCCGGGCAGCCCCCAAUCCCGCGCCGCCCGGACCCCCUCCUCCUCCCUCCCUCCUCCCUCCGCCCCCUCCCCGCGGGACUCCGGCGUCCCCGCCCCCCAGUCCUCCCUCCCCUCCCCUCCAGCAUGGUGCUCGCGGCCCCGCUGCUGCUGGGCUUCCUGCUCCUCGCCCUGGAGCUGCGGCCCCGGGGGGAGGCGGCCGAGGGCCCCGCGGCGGCGGCGGCGGCGGCGGCGGCGGCGGCAGCGGCGGGGGUCGGGGGGGAGCGCUCCAGCCGGCCAGCCCCGUCCGUGGCGCCCGAGCCGGACGGCUGCCCCGUGUGCGUUUGGCGGCAGCACAGCCGCGAGCUGCGCCUAGAGAGCAUCAAGUCGCAGAUCUUGAGCAAACUGCGGCUCAAGGAGGCGCCCAACAUCAGCCGCGAGGUGGUGAAGCAGCUGCUGCCCAAGGCGCCGCCGCUGCAGCAGAUCCUGGACCUACACGACUUCCAGGGCGACGCGCUGCAGCCCGAGGACUUCCUGGAGGAGGACGAGUACCACGCCACCACCGAGACCGUCAUUAGCAUGGCCCAGGAGACGGACCCAGCAGUACAGACAGAUGGCAGCCCUCUCUGCUGCCAUUUUCACUUCAGCCCCAAGGUGAUGUUCACAAAGGUACUGAAGGCCCAGCUGUGGGUGUACCUACGGCCUGUACCCCGCCCAGCCACAGUCUACCUGCAGAUCUUGCGACUAAAACCCCUAACUGGGGAAGGGACCGCAGGGGGAGGGGGCGGAGGCCGGCGUCACAUCCGUAUCCGCUCACUGAAGAUUGAGCUGCACUCACGCUCAGGCCAUUGGCAGAGCAUCGACUUCAAGCAAGUGCUACACAGCUGGUUCCGCCAGCCACAGAGCAACUGGGGCAUCGAGAUCAACGCCUUUGAUCCCAGUGGCACAGACCUGGCUGUCACCUCCCUGGGGCCGGGAGCCGAGGGGCUGCAUCCAUUCAUGGAGCUUCGAGUCCUAGAGAACACAAAACGUUCCCGGCGGAACCUGGGUCUGGACUGCGACGAGCACUCAAGCGAGUCCCGCUGCUGCCGAUAUCCCCUCACAGUGGACUUUGAGGCUUUCGGCUGGGACUGGAUCAUCGCACCUAAGCGCUACAAGGCCAACUACUGCUCCGGCCAGUGCGAGUACAUGUUCAUGCAAAAAUAUCCGCAUACCCAUUUGGUGCAGCAGGCCAAUCCAAGAGGCUCUGCUGGGCCCUGUUGUACCCCCACCAAGAUGUCCCCAAUCAACAUGCUCUACUUCAAUGACAAGCAGCAGAUUAUCUACGGCAAGAUCCCUGGCAUGGUGGUGGAUCGCUGUGGCUGCUCUUAAGGUGGGGGAUAGAGGAUGCCUCCCCCACAGACCCUACCCCAAGACCCCUAGCCCUGCCCCCAUCCCCCCAAGCCCUAGAGCUCCCUCCACUCUUCCCGCGAACAUCACACCGUUCCCCGACCAAGCCGUGUGCAAUACAACAGAGGGAGGCAGGUGGGAAUUGAGGGUGAGGGGUUUGGGGGAAAGGGGAAGCAGGGGCAUAGUCAGGGUGGGGAGUGUUUGAAGUUUGCAGAUGAGAAGGUUUGACAAAAAGACAGAGAGAUGUAGAGACAGUGAUAGAGACAGAGGAACAAAAAGAGCAGCAGUGAGAAGGCAAAGAGAGAGGCAGAAGAGACAGACGAGGCAGAGACAAAACACUGAGAAAGAGACUGAAAUGGAGUAAUAAAUGAAAGCCCCACACCAAGCCUCCUUUCUUCCACUGGCAAGGUGAGGGGCUUGGUAUAGUUUGGGGAGAUCCCCUGACUAUUCAGUAGGAGAAGAAAUCAAAAAUCCAUUCUUUUCUCCUUCUCUCCCUCCAACAGUGGCCAGGGGAAGGGGAAGUGAGGGCAGGGGCAAAAAGAUUUGGGAAUUUUUAUUUAUUUAUUUAUUGUGACUUUUCAUUUUUUUGGUAUUUGGCUUUACUGGAAUAGGAGGGCCCCUGCCCACUGUGCCCCGUUUAUCCCUUAUUCCCCAAACCCUGCUCUCCCCAACACCUACUCACUUAAGCACUUGUAUAAAGCCUCCAGGGUUGGGAAUGGGAGUAAAGGGCAAGAGGGCGGACACAUGAAGUUUAGUUUCUAACCCAUCAUCACCCUAACUCAACCUUUUCUGAGCCAAAUGGCUUGAAUUGAAGCCAGUUGUCAUGGAAAUAGUAAGAGGUUAGGGUUUAAGAGCUGGGGAUGCGGGGGUGGGAGAGAGAACCCUCAACAUCCAGGAUCUAUAUAAUGAGAGCUACUUUAAACCCUCAGGUCCACCCUCAUGAUGCUGAGUUAUUUAGCCAGAGGGUGCAGCCUGCUUAUGCCCAAAUUCCCUCAGCCAAGAGAGAGACCAAAGAGCCUCUGGAAUGGCCCUGCUCCCAGCCUCUAUCUUCAGGUCAAUUAGAGAGAGUAUAGAGACCCCAGAGUCCCCUGGGUCUGGAAAGCGUUAGGAGAGGUCAAGAAAGGAGCAGUAAGGAGGCUGAAGGUUACAGGGCAUUUGAAUCCAAAUCACUGCUCUGGGCUAGGGAAUAGAGCCAGCAGACCAAGGUGGGAAGGAUUCUGGAAGGGGGACAUUUUAGUCUCCUAACCCCAAAGCUCAGGGUGGAAGAGGGGAGAACAAGGAAGCAGAGUGUAUAAUUAUUUUUUCCUUUUAUUUUUGGAAUCUAACAGUACCUGGCAGCAGGGAGGGGAAAGUACAGUGGGGAAAAGCAUCUGACAAGGCCAGUUAGAACAGAGGAUGGGAAGGAUGGAGACUCCCGGGCUUGGAAGGCUAGGAAGCAGGCAGAGACUGGUUGCCAUUUCAAGUCACUAGCUAGGCCCAUUCAUUCCUCCCACAACCCUGACCCAUUCUCCUCUGGACUCACUGUGCCUCAGUUUCUUCCCCUCAAUGGAAUGAGAAAUGACAGCACCCGCCACAGCCAAGAGAUGAAUUCUGAGCACUUACCACGGGCACUUUAUGGACAUAAAAUACCUCUCGCUGUGGGACAGAUAACCAGGGCACCAGAGUAGUGGUGAAGAGAUGUGAGGCUUAAGAGGAGUCACAGGCUUCAGAGUACAAGUUCCCCUCUGCCUCCCAGCUGGACAGUGCCUAGAAGCCAAGGAGUUGAGAAUCUCCUGAUCCACACCCUAUCCUUACUUCACCACCAGGCCUCUUGGCUCCAGGCAAGAGCUUAGAGGAUGUCAGGAGAGGUGGGGGUAAGAAUCUUCAGCAAAACUGUCACUCUAAGUAGAGCCAGCAGUUACGGGUCUGAUAAAAACAGUACUGAACUAAAGUAAAGCCCAAGCUGGUGAGCAAAACUGGAUGGCUCAUUCUUCCCAAGAGCAUGACUCUCCCCCUUGGCCAGUUGGUGGAAGGGGCAAAGGUAUGUGACCACCCUUGAGAAGGUGAUGUUGGUGAGCUUUAACAUCUUAUUCCUAUUCUUAUAGUGAGAAAGUGAAACAAGAUCUUUCAGUAGAGGAAUGGGCAGGGCUGUUAGGCUCUUCAGCUUGCCUUCACCCAUAUAGCAGCUAUGCUAACCCCAAGCCUCUCUGGCCCUGUUCUUCAUCCUUCCUUCUGCCCCAAUCCUGAAGGACAAGACACACCCGGCCAUCAACACCACUCACAUUUCCUUGGUGGAAGGAAAGGAACAGAGAAGUGAAGAACAGAUACCUCCCUCCAAGGUCAAAUGCCUCGUGAUCUUGGCAGAGUAGGGAUUGGGCAAUAAGCAUCAGGUAUCUUCCCUCUACAGAUUCUAGAGAGCUGGGGCAUUAAAUAUGGGGGACACUUAGAAUACAGCUCCUUAAAUACCACCAAAUAAAGACCUUUGUGUGUGUGUGGUGGGUGGGGGGGGGGCAGGGGUCUUUCUCUUAUGAACAUAAAUCUGUGAGCUGAAGUCUCAUUCCCCUGUUCCUCCCUACCCCCAAAGAGGCACAGAGUGAAGGGACUUGGGGGGCACAGCUCAGCAACCCAGUGGGAGUUAGCACCCCCUCCCACCUUAUGAUGUGUGUGGACCUGGCCAGUGCCCCUCUGAACAUAUCAUUAUUAGUGUAAUUAUCAUUUAUUUUGUGUAUUUGUCACAUUGUGUGCAUGACAGCCUUUGUUAAGGGUGUCUGAGGAGUAUGGAGCUGACAGGGGCAUUGGAAUGCCAGGAAAGAACUUCUUCAACUGAGAUCAAGGCUUCCUGGAGGGAACCACUGCAAAAAGGCCAUCAGGCAGUUUUCAAGUUAUGUGACAGAGGGCAAAGACGGCCAUAGGGUGCUCUGAGUUUUGGGAUGGUCACAUGACACAAUCCAGCACUUGAACCUGAAAAAAAAAAUAAAAGCGGUCAAAGAGUUUAGAAUUCAGUGCUGAGCUCUUCUCCCUAAUCAAGUGCCACAUUUACACCUUGGAGAACCGGAGGUGAAGAGGAUCUGAGACAGGAAACCUCGUGUUCAAUGACUAAGAAGAUGGGGUCCUGGAGCAAGACAGAAAACACUAAGGGCAUGGUGGUAUAAGGUUUGGGACAUGCAGGCCAAGGAAGGAUGGAAAGAGGACAGGAAACUGGGGGUACCUAGAACAACCCCUCUCUGAAAAGCUUGAGCCAAAACAGUCCCAAAGACAACAAGACCCCUCUCCCAGCCUCCACAGAAUGGAAGAUCUAAAGGUUCUCUUGAGAUGAUCCAGCUAGUAUGGAAGAUCUAAAGGUUCUCUUGAGAUGAUCCAGCUAGUGUCCUAUUCUCCUGCAGUCCCUGUUCCUAGGUUUCCUCAACGAAGUUUGACAAAAAUCUAAACCAACAUAGCCAACGAACUUGCCUUGUUACACAAGAGUGGCUAAAAUAGCAUCUCAAAUAUUCUUUCAGUUCACUGUAAAAAUUUUUCCCAUGUACCUAGAGCACAAUUCCCCAGGAAUAUGAGUUGGGAAUGGCAAAAGAAUAUUGCCUGACUCACAUUUUUCAAAAAUAAGGAAAGCUGGCUGGGCGCAGUGGCUUACAUCUGUAAUCCCAGCACUUUGGGGGGCCGAGGCGGGCGGAUCAUGCAAGGUCCGGAGUUCGAGACCAUGCUGGCCAACAUUGUGAAACCUCAUCUCUACUAAAAUACCCAAAAUUAGCCGGGCGUGGUGGCGUGCGCCUGUAAUCCCAGCUACAUGGAAGGCUGAGGCAGAAGAAUCGCUUGAACCCAGGUGGCGGAGGUUGCAGUGAGCUGAGAUCGCACCACUGCACUCUAGCAUGGUGACAGAGUGAGACUCCCAUCUCCAAAAAAAAAAAAAAAAAAAAAAAAAGGAAAGCAGGACCCAGUGGUGUGCUCCUGUAGUUCCAGCUAUUCAGGAGGCUGUGGCAGGAGGACCACUUGAGGCCAGAGGGUCAAGGCUGCAGUGUGCUAUAAUUGGGCCUGUAAAUAGCCACUGUACUCCAAGCUGAGCAACACAGUAAGACACUGUCUCUAAAAAUAAUUAAAGUAAAAUAAAAAUAAGGAAAGCUCCUGUGACAUCAACCUGAUCCAGAAUUGGGGACAGCGCUACUGCGGGUUCAAUGUACUGCCAUGUUUUCCCUGUCUUAUCAGUUCUAUCAGCACACUGACCCCACUCGAGACCAACUACAAGACUAAGGCUGGAAGUGGUUGAGUAGCAGAAGUGUUAUGUAUUCUAUCUUCCCAAGGGAACCAUAUCCACAUCUACCCCUAACUUUGGCCUGAGCUGAAAAUGGGUUUUCUCUCCCUGUGGCUCAUUUGUUUCCUAUAUUGAGAGAACACCCAAAAAAAGACUACUCAAGAUGACUUUUUACAAGUCUUUUCUUUAUCCUAAAACAUCCUCCAACCGAAGGCAUGGGAAGCUAUCCUAUACUCUGACCUUGCCUAUAUUUUAAAUGGCAGGGGCCCCAAGCUAAGAAUCAGCAGGCAGUGGCAUCUACAGCUUCUGGUCUGUAGUGGCGUAGAAGCAGGAAAAUCAAUGCUCCAAAGCAACAAUGUCCAGCUUUCCUGCCAGUGAGCUGGGCUUGAGGGAGUGAAUGGGACUCUUUCUGCCUUUUCUUUUUCUCAAAAUACGACUGCAUUAACUGGGUGUAUGCACACACAAACAUGUUCAAACUAGGGCACUCAUACCUAGCUAGAACCUACUCAGGGAAAGAAAUAUGUAUUUCCACAGUACCCUGAUCACCCAGUAAAAGCUAAUAUUUAUUGAAUAAUUACUAUGCAAAUUAUGGUAAGCAAAUUGUAGUGUGAAUACAUGAUAUGAGAAUAUCACUUAAUUCACACAGCAACCUUCACAAUGGGGUUCCUUUUGGUACAGUCUGAAAAGAGAAUGAUUAUCUGCGCAGGGUCUCAGAGCUAGUGUGGUAGAAUAAGAAAUUAAACCUAAGUAGUUGCUAAACAAUAUUACAUUCUAAUCUAUCCUAUUGAAAGUGAUCCGGGAGGUAGAAACCUAAAUACAGGAAUAACAUAAGGGAAAGAGAUAACAAGAAAGUUAGGGACACCUUGGACUCAAAGAAUCUGGAAAGAUGUGAAACCUGUAAUUUUAAAUCCCUUUGGAAGGGAAAAACAAGAAAAGUCUAGAUAUGGCAAGAGAAGGGGAGGUUAAAUUUUGGGGGGAUUCCAAUAAUCAGAAAUAAGUGGCAUUGCCAGAGGCCCUCAUAUAAGAGAACAGCAAAAAAGUUAUCCUCCCUUAAGUUCCUCCCUCACUCCUCAUAUCAGACACAGCAAGAGAACUCAGCUCAACACCAAGAAGUCCUGCCCUUAUUCACACCUUCCUUCCUAUAGCCCUCAUCCUCACAGAAGCUUCUAGCCUCUAUCUUCAGCAGUUCUUAAGAGGUGGGGUGGGGGGCUGGGCAGUUUAGAGUGAGAGUGGAAAAAAAGAAUAAUCCUAGAGAACCAUAAAAAAGUACAGAUUUACAGCUGAGGAAGCUAGUUCUCCCCACAGCUUUUAUAGACUCCCUCAUUAAGAGCUUCCAGGUAUGCAGAGAAUGUCACAGCUUCAGGAAUUGGAAUCAGUUAACCACAUCUGGAUGCUGGAUCAACUAUAGUAGGGAAACGGGGAGAGGAAGGAAGGGUACUAAGAUCUCAGGUAAACAAUUACAAGCCUCAAUGUCUGUUCCAUCUCCAAACGGAAUUACUAUUUUAAAACUGAAUUGGGAAAAAGGCAUCCUGAACUAUUCAUGCUCAAAGAGUAUGUGGAGAAUGACUAUAAUGAGAUAGGAAGGGGAGGACUUCAUCUGGCUUGGAGGUUAGAGACUUCUGACCAACAUAGGAACAGCUGCUGAAAUGGGAUGAAAGAGGUUAAUAAGAAAAAAAAAAAAAUCCUCACAAAUUGGAAAACACUGUUCAAAGAUCUAGGGGAAGUAAGAUGAGUGAGGAGAAUAAUUAGGCUUCAAGAAGAGAAUCCUGGCAAGUAAGGCUGAAUAUCUUUCUGGAAGGUUAUAGAGGAUAAAGAGACGAAGAAAACUUCCAAAAGAUCCACUGUUCCACUUCAUAAUCAGCAUCUGCUCUAUUCCCUCAUGUAUUUUUCUCUUUUUAAAACCAUAUUCAGGAAGAAACCAUUAGUGAAUCUAUAAUCUCUCAAGUUACAAAUCAGAUCUAUUCUGUUUUCAGAUGAAGGCAGAGUAGAGAGAGGAAAAGCUAGCCCCAAGAUCAGAGCCUGAGGUAAAGAAAAGGAAGGCAGACAGAAAAGAGGGAAAAGGGAAGGUCAUUCCAAUUUUAAGGUUUAUUUGGUUGAAGAGGUGUCAAAAAUUUAACCAGCAUUCCCUUUUGUUCACUUCUCCAAAGUCUCAGAAUGGGGCAAACUUCACAACAAAUGGGCAGCAGUUUUUGGAUCUGCUCUCCAAGGCACAAUUUUUCUAAAUUAUCUAAACUUUAGGUCCCUGCUUUCCUCACCAACCAGAGACUUUGGAGAAAUAAAGAGAUAUCUUGACAUUAGAAAGGUGAUCAAACUAUUACCAUUUCAUUAAGCACAAAACCAGGCAGGUUUUAGUAGAAAUAAGGAUAAAGGAUUACACCACAGCAACAUGGGACCUGAUCAUAGUACCAAAGUCUUCAGGUAAGGUGUCAGGCUCCUAAGUCUUAUUACCAAAAAUAGCUCAAACAAAAACCGAGCUUAUAUAAAGAUUAAGAGGAGAAAUUCUGCAAUAACAUAUCCAAAAAGAUUAAGCAGGUUUCAGAUCUACAUGAACUUGAAGCCUCCAGUUCCACUGCUUAUGUUCCCAAUGAUUUAGCUAACAAUGCGUAACAGCUCUGACAUCCUCUGUCAUGCUUUGAUUCUGCAUACAAAAUUUCUUCUGUCUCUGAGGGAUAUCCAGCCCAUCUCCCUUCCUGAACUGACUGACCAACAUAGUAUCGUAUCACAUCACCCUUGAAAUCAGGGCCCUUUUCCUUUAAUGUGGGACCCUGGACUCCAUUUUAUCCAAGAAAAAGUCUGCAUUAUUAGCUAAUAACAGAAGGCUACUAAUCACUGCCCUUGUAUUUAUAUCCUUUGCAACACCUAAAACCUCCCAUGUUCUGUUUUAUUUCAGUGGGUCACUACAAGCUGCUGGAGCAAAGACUUGGUGGGUGGGUAACUUAACCUCUUCACAGAGGAUAAAAAAUGCUUGUGAGUAUGACAGAAGGGAAUAAACAGGCUUAAAGGGUAAACUCAGUCCUUUUCCUUGUCUUCUCUUCUAAGGGAUAAAGGUAUUAUGGCCAAUUCUCUAUAAUAUUUGCCCCUGAAGCUCCCCUUAUCUGGUCUAAUCUAGCUCCAAUAAAUCAAAGGAGCACCUAAUAAAACA